CGCGGGCGCCCUUGUUUGGGAGCGCGGCCGGCGCGCCCGUUUUGAAGCUGCCCUGAGCAGCGCGGGCCGGACCGCGCCCCCUCCUCGGUCCCCGCGCCCCGCGAGUCCGCGCAGUUCCCGAGGCGCGGGCCCUGUUCCCUGCGCCGCGCCCCCUCAGCGGGCCGUGCUCGCAUCACCGAGGUCGGUCCGGGGCGGACCGAAGCCCCCGGGGCGGGGCGGGGCGCGGGCGUCCGGGGGCGCCGCGGGCCCAGCCCCCGCCAUGCCGCCCGGCAAAGUGCUGCAGCCGGUCCUGAAGAUGAAGGUGGACGAGCUGUUCCUGUACUGGCUCAGCGAGGCCAGCACGCAGCGGAUGCUGCAGGACUGCCUGCGCCGGAUCAAGGCGCCCGGGCGGGACCAGCCGACCCCGGGGGACGGGGAGCAGCCCGGGGCCUGGCCCACAGCCCCGCUCGCCGCCCCCCGGCCCAGCGGGCUCGAACCCCCGGGAACCCCCGGGCCGGGCCCUGCGCUGCCCCUGGGCGCCGCCUCCAGCCCCAGGAACGCGCCCCACGUUCGAGGCACCCGUAGAUCCGCAGGGACGAGAGUAGUUCAGACACGGAAAGAAGAGCCUCUGCCCCCGGCCACGAGCCAAAGCAUUCCGACCUUCUACUUCCCCAGAGGACGCCCGCAGGACUCCGUCAACGUGGAUGCCGUCAUCAGCAAGAUCGAGAGCACCUUCGCCCGGUUCCCCCACGAGAGGGCCACCAUGGAUGACAUGGGCCUGGUGGCCAAGGCCUGCGGCUGCCCCCUCUACUGGAAGGGGCCGCUCUUCUAUGGCGCCGGCGGGGAGCGCACGGGCUCCGUGUCCGUCCACAAGUUCGUCGCCAUGUGGAGAAAAAUCCUCCAGAACUGCCACGACGACGCGGCCAAGUUCGUCCAUCUGCUCAUGAGCCCCGGCUGCAACUACCUGGUGCAGGAGGACUUUGUCCCCUUCUUGCAGGACGUGGUGAACACGCACCCGGGGCUGUCGUUCCUGAAGGAGGCGUCCGAGUUCCACUCGCGCUACAUCACCACGGUCAUCCAGCGGAUCUUCUACGCCGUGAACCGGUCCUGGUCCGGCAGGAUCACCUGCGCCGAGCUGCGGAGGAGCUCCUUCCUGCAGAAUGUGGCGCUGCUGGAGGAGGAGGCGGACAUCAACCAGCUGACCGAAUUCUUCUCGUACGAGCAUUUCUACGUCAUCUACUGCAAGUUCGGGGAGCUGGACACGGACCACGACCUGCUCAUCGACGCGGACGACCUGGCGCGGCACAAUGACCACGCCCUUUCUACCAAGAUGAUAGACAGGAUCUUCUCAGGAGCAGUCACACGAGGCAGAAAAGUGCAGAAGGAAGGGAAGAUCAGCUAUGCCGACUUUGUCUGGUUUUUGAUCUCUGAGGAAGACAAAAAAACACCGACCAGCAUCGAGUACUGGUUCCGCUGCAUGGACCUGGACGGGGACGGCGCCCUGUCCAUGUUCGAGCUCGAGUACUUCUACGAGGAGCAGUGCCGAAGGCUGGACAGCAUGGCCAUCGAGGCCCUGCCCUUCCAGGACUGCCUCUGCCAGAUGCUGGACCUGGUCAAGCCGAGGACUGAAGGGAAGAUCACGCUGCAGGACCUGAAGCGCUGCAAGCUGGCUAACGUCUUCUUCGACACCUUCUUCAACAUCGAGAAGUACCUCGACCACGAGCAGAAAGAGCAGAUCUCCCUGCUCAGGGACGGUGACAGCGGCGGCCCCGAGCUCUCGGACUGGGAGAAGUACGCGGCCGAGGAGUACGACAUCCUGGUGGCCGAGGAGACUGCGGGAGAGCCCUGGGAGGACGGAGAUGGGGUUUCACCGUGUUGCCCAGGUUGGUCUUGGAUGCCUGAGCUCGAGGGUUCUCCCCGCCUCGGUCCCCCAACGUGCCGGAAUUACAGGUGUGAGCCCCUGCCCAGCCUUGAGUGAGCUUUGCUGGUUUGUGUGUUUCGGAAACUUGCCCGUUCCCAUCAGUGGGUUAUUGUUGGUAUUUCCUGCUCGUGACUCUGAUGUCUGCAGAAUCCAGUGAUAGCGUCUCUCACGCUCCUGAUACUGACUUUGUGUGUGAUCAGUGAGGCGAGGGGCCGACGAGGUUCACUCCUCUUCCCAGGGAACCACGGGUGUUUCUCCCCUUUGUUCUGCUGUUUUCCUUGAGUAUCUUCAGGCAGCGACGUGGGCCAUGGACACCGCAGCCCGCGGCCUUCUGAUUUUGGUGCAGCUCAAAAUACUUUCUGGUUACCGUUGGGUUCCCGACCCAUGGGUUCCAUGGACGUGCAUUUUAACCCCUGCUCCCCCAUCAGCCGCCCCGUCCGAUUCCUGCCAAGCAGCACAGGGCCCCUGCGGCCCACCCUGGGCCGUCUGUCCUGUGUGUCCGUCCUCCUCGUGGUCAUUGUUUGCACGGUGGCUCUGACCUGGCAGCCAACCUCUGGGUCCCCACAACUUCCCAGUCUCUGCCUUCUCCUGUCGGACACCCUAAGGCAGCUGUGGCCCCCAGACCUAGCCUGGAUGGGUGUGCGCCUGUCCCCACCACCGUCUGUCACCUCUGCUCCCCACCUGACCAGUGUCCACCCCCACGGCUGCCCGGCUUUGUGUCUGCGGCACAGCCAGCAGCACGCUGGGGUCGACUGCCUUCACCGUGUCCACGCCUGCUCCGGCAGUGGGAGCUCAGGUCCGUGGGGGUGACCGCGGGGAGCUCAGUGCCAGGCUGUCGGGGGCGUCUUGGAAAGCAGAGGUGUCCCCACAGGAUCUCUGAGAGUCUGUGUGGUCCGUGGCCGCGCUGGGUUCCCCGGAGCAGCGCCCGACGUCACUGCCGAGACCUUAAGGGAAGGCGCGCGUCCAGUCCUCGCACUG